CUCUCUCUCCGGUCCGUGCCUCCAAGAUGACAAAGAAAAGAAGGAACAAUGGUCGUGCCAAAAAGGGCCGCGGCCACGUGCAGCCUAUUCGCUGCACUAACUGUGCCCGAUGCGUGCCCAAGGACAACGCCAUUAAGAAAUUCGUCAUUCGAAACAUAGUGGAGGCCGCAGCAGUCAGGGACAUUUCUGAAGCGAGCGUCUUCGAUGCCUAUGUGCUUCCCAAGCUGUAUGUGAAGCUACAUUACUGUGUGAGUUGUGCAAUUCACAGCAAAGUAGUCAGGAAUCGAUCUCGUGAAGCCCGCAAGGACCGAACACCCCCACCUCGAUUUAGACCUGCGGGUGCUGCCCCACGUCCCCCACCAAAGCCCAUGUAAGGAGCUGAGUUCUUAAAGACUGAAGACAGGCUAUUCUCUGGAGAAAAAUAAAAUGGAAAUUGUACUUAAAAAAAAAAAAAAAAAAGCCCAGGACCAGAUGGCUUCACUGGUAAAUUCUACCAAACAUUUACAGAAUUCACACCAGUCCUCCUGAAACUCUUCUAAAGAAUGAAGAAGAAGGAACAUUUCAGUGUUGAGCAUCACCCUGAUACUAAGGCCAAAGACACUCCAAGAAAGAAAACUACAGACUAAUAUUCUUGAUGAAGAUCGAUGCCAAAAUCCUAAACAACACACUAGCAAACAGAAUUCAACAACACAUUAAAAGGAUUAUAUGCAAUGGCCAAGUGGGAUUUAUUCCUGGAAUGCAAGGAUGUUUCAAUAUAAGAAAAUCAAUCAAUGUAAUACACUACAUUAACAGAAUGAAGGAAAAAACACACAAUCACUUCAAUUGAUACAGAAAAAGCAUUUGACAAGAUUCAACACAACUUCAUGAUUUAAAAACAGUCAACAAAGGAACAGAAGGAAAUUACCUCAACAUCAUAAAGGCAGUAUAUGAAAAGCCCACAGCUAACAUGAUACUCAGUGAUGCCAGAAUGAAAGCUUUUCUUCUGAGAUCAGGAACAAGAAAAGGAUGCUGCUUUCAUCAGUUCUGUUGAACAUAGUUCUGGGAGUCCUAGCUGGAGCAAUCAGGCAAGAAAAAGAAAUUUAAAAGGCAUCCAAGUCAGAGGUAAGAAGUAAAAUUAACUCUAUUUGUAAACAAUAUGGUCCUGUAUAGAAAAUGUAAACAUUUCACCUUAAAACUUUUAGAACUAAUAAGCAAAUUCAGUGAAGUUGCAGGAGACAAAAUUCACACAAAUAAUUAUUGCAUUUUUAUACACUAACAAUAAGCAAUCUGAAAAGACAAACUAUUCCAUUUAUGAUAGCAUCAAAAAGAAUAAAAUACUUAGGAAUAAACUUAACCAAGCAGGCAAGAUGUGUACACUGAAAAGUACAACACAUUGCUGAAAGCAAUUAAAGAGGACAUAAAUAAAUGGAAAGACAUCCCAUGUUCAUGGAUUGGAAGACAAUAUUGUUCAGAUGUCAAUAUUUCCUAAAGUGAUCUACAGAUUAAUGCAGUCCUUUAAUGCAGAAAGAGGAAAACCCAAUCCAAAAAUGUAUAUGGAAAUAUCAAAGGACCUUAAAUAGACAAUGUGAUCUUGGAAAAGAACAAUGUUGGAGGUCUCAUACUUCCUGACUUCAAAACUUAUCAUAAAGUUACUGUAAUCAAAAUAGCAUAGAACAGGAAUUCCUCCUUAUCUGUGGUUUUGCUUUCCGUGGUUAUUGUUUAAUGGGUACAAAGUUUCAGUUUUGCAAGAUGAAAAGGUUCUGGAGACCUUUUUCACAACUCAAAUAUACUUAACACUACUGAACUGAACACUUGAAAAUAGUUAUGAUAAAUUUUAUGUUAUGUGUAUUUUAUCACAAUUUUUAAAACUCCACAAAUUAAAAAACAGGAAAUACAGAGAAGGAUUUGGUUUAUCAGAUAAAAUUUAAAACAAGUAGGGAACAAAAAGCAUAGGGAAGUGUAGGGUGCUUUGCAAACCAUCUCUGCCAUUGCAGAGCCUGAGUCCUCCACCAUACUUGACAGGGUCACCUCCCUUGGGCCUUGGGGUCAGUGCAAGUGACAGAGCCAGAGAGGCUUUUGGAGUCCAGCAGGCCCAGGCUCAGUUCCUGCUGCUGCCUCUCACCAGCUUCGGGCCAGAGCCCUCAUCUUAGUUUCUUCAUCUGUUAAAUGAAGGUAAUACCACCUACUUUACAGAGUUGAGAGCAUUAAAUAAACUGAGAUUACACAGGCUACUUAGUGCGGGGCCCAGUACACCCAGGUGAACCUCGGUCGUCGGUAAGCAAGGUCCCAGAAGUCCUCCCUGGGAAUUAGCCUUCUUCAGAAACACUAUCCUCCAACUCUCUUCUCCUCUUACCUCUGUCCUAAGCCUGCUUGUCCACUCUUGGAUGAAAUAUUUUUCUUCCUUUGCAGUUGAAUCCCCGGAAUAGUGAAAACAAUGACCAUUGCGUGCUGAGUACCUGCUCUGUCCUGGCAUCUUACAACUCUGUUCCAAAGUCUGUGCUGCUUCCAUAGGACUGUUCUCACUUCUUUCCAUUUUGCAAGUUCUCAGCCUGGCGGCAGUCUCCCUGCCCGAGUGGAUGGUGCCACCACCUCUUACUGAAGGAGCGGUUUCUGAGGGAGAGUGCCUGUGCUGUGCAGCUGUCUCCCGCGAGGCGCCCUUUGACAAGUGUGUCUUCUGUCUCCCCUCAAUGACACUGUGGCUUCAUGGAGUCUCAUUGCAUGCCCAGCACUUAGCACAGGGCAUCCCUGCAUGGCUGCGUUGUUCCCUGCAUGGCUGCAUUUAGGCUUUCCUUUUCCUGCAAGUGCUGCCUCGUCUUUCCUUUCUCUCGUCUCAGCAGCAGGAAGAGCAAGUUCUUUCUCUGCCUCCCCGCUGCCUGGCUCCUUCAGCUAUCACCAGCCAUCCCCUCUACCCAGCCCUCACUCUGGUGCCACAAUUGCUACUUUCCUGGCUUCUUCACGGGGACCUGACAUACCCUUGAGUCUCCUGUACCUGAAGAAAACCUCCUUGCCAUCCUUCUAAGCAAGCAGUUUCUGUCUUGUCGCUUCCUUUCUGGCUCACAUCAAGUCUCUCAGAGGAAGGGGCUAGGGCUGGCGGUGCAGCAAGGGAGAAGACAGGGAGGACAGGCCCUGUGUCCAGCUUCCUCCUAAUGCUACUCAAACGACCCACAAGGACAGUGGAGGAAAGCGGGCGACACGCUUCUGGAAGACGGAAAACAGAAGUGAGUGACAGCAGACUUAACCUAGAGACACCCAAAACUUAAGCUCCUGCACAGUGAGAGGCUGACAAGUAGUCAGCUGAGCAGUGUCUGCAACGCUGGAGGAGUCCAGAACCGCAGGCCACAGAGGCAAGGACAGGCCAAGACACGGAAAGGCUGGGAGUGUGCACAAGGUGCAGGGAGACCCCACUGCUUCCCCUCACACCUGGCAGAGGAUGGCGGGUUCCUUUCUGGAGAGCCUGACAAGAACACCUCCGCUGGGGACACAGGCCUAGCUGAGUGGUGGUGAGGUGGCACCCUGAAAACAAGCAUUGGGGGAAAGUGCAGAGCUCCCAGCGCCGCUCCCCAGAGUCCCGUGUGAGGCCUGCCACCUGACAGCUCAGCCUCACUUCCAAAGAGUGGCUCAGCUUUCCCAGCCAAGAUCACAUGUGAAGAAAAUCUCUUGAAACACAGAUACCAAAACAGAGAGAAAAGAGGGAGUUAGGAGAAAUGGAGGCAAUGAAGGGAAUGAAGAAAACUUAAAAAAUAUAUAUAUAUUGAGCCUGUGAAUGAACAAGAAGUUGAAAAAAAAAACACACAACAAGAAAAAUAUAUUGGAAAUAAAUAUCAUGGCAAAAAAAUUUUUAAUAGAAGAAAUGCAAGAUAAAGCAGAAUAUAAUAUAGACCUGGAGGAAAGGAGAAAAUAUAAAAACAUUGGAGGCUGAAGUCAGGACCUCCACUGCCGGAAUAUUGGGAGAGCCAGAAAGAGAACAGAGAGGAAGGAGGGGUAAGAAAAUGCCCCCGUGAUCCAGGAUAAGGAGCAUUCAGAUCAAAAUUCCAGCACAAUCAAUGAAAACAGAGUCUACAUCAUCAGAAAAUUCUAGAAUCUGAGGGAUAAAAGGAAGCCCUUAAGAGCCUCCAGGGAAGAGCUCGAGUCACACACACAGGGGACCUGGAUCACAGCACACUGACUUCUCUGCAAGAACUCGGAAAGUUAGAAGACAAUGAAGAAAUGUCUUUAAAGUUCUGAGGGAAAUGAUUUCUAGAAUCCUCUACGCAGCCAUGUUAUUAACCAAAAGUGGGAGAGAAUACACUUCAGCAAAAUGUGGCCAACAUCCCAGCCAGAGGACGGGACAGGAAUGAGGGUGGCCUGGAUGGCAGCGACACAGAGAGCCCAGACUAGAGCUGGCAGGGAGGACCUUCCAGCGGAUGGUCAGGACCCGGGUUCUGGCCAUGCUCUCAGAAACUGCGAGGCUGAAUUACAAUCCUAGAAACUAAGCGAAAUGCAAAACAAACAAAAAAAACAAACUUGAAGCAAUUUUUAAUUUCAAGGAAAACAUAAAGUUGUCCAAGAAAGGAAAUGUAAUCAUAGUAUGCUCUGUGUCUUAGCCAAGAGCCGUGUUUGCAUGGUUCUAAUGCCGAAAUAGAUCUGGGUCUGACCCAAAACUAUGAUGAGUCUGUUGGGAGGAUGGCGGGAUGUGGUAGGAGAGCCAAGGGUCAGGCUUCUACAGUGAUGACAGCAGCGGCACACGCUACAUGUCAGCAGAUCACACAGGACCACGUGUGUUGGUACCCACCGCGGUCUCUGAGGCAGGCUGCUACUGUGACUUCAGUUUACAGUUGAGGAAGCUGAGGCACAGAGAGGUUAUAUGAUCUGCCUAAAGUCACACAGUUAAAGUCUGUGCUUUAGAACCACUAUGCUCACCCACUUUUUGAGUAGAAGGGCAAGAUAUGAUUUAAGACAUCAAGAAGUAGCAGCGUAAGUAACAAUAUGGAGAUAAAUGCUGAACACAACAGUUAAAAGCCUUAAAAGUGUUGCCUCCAGGGAGUGGAAAGGGGUAGGAAACUUCAUUUUUCUUACAAAGCAAUCUAUUGACAUUUUGGACACAUGCCAUUUUAAAAAACUGCAUCAGGGAAAGCCAGGCAGGCACCUGGCAGUGGAGAGCUGGUCUGCAGUGUGACUACGGCCCUGCCCGGCUGGCUGGUCCUAGAUCGCCACCAGCCUGGGACUCGGCUUCCUCACCUGCAGGUGCUGGACCAAACAGUUUCCAAGUUCUCUUCUGGCCCUUCAUGUUCCAGCAACAAACAAGACCAGUGAUUUAGAGAGCACGUGUGCUAUAACGACAACCAGACAGAGUGAUGUGACAGACUGAGUAGGCCCUGCCUACUACUCCUGCACCCUCCAGUCUGUGGCCCAGACCCAGGCAAGUGGUAAAUAUUUACCUUCACGCUGGAGCCAAGAUCGCUGCGGGGAGUCCCGUGAAGCACCACUGCCCUCUAAGACCUUGGAAGGGGAAACACCAGAAGGUGUGGGUGCUGAGCUCCGCUGCGUCAGACUGCCAGGACCUGAGUGGAACUCAGUGCUGAAACCUGGGUUCUCACUGCAGCUGGAUAGCAGCUCUGCCCGGAUGGCCCUAGUCUUCGUGUACGGCACCCUGAAGCGGGGUCAGCCCAACCACAGGGUCCUGCGGGACGGCGCCCACGGCUCCGCAGCCUUUCGGGCGCGCGGCCGCACGCUGGAGCCCUACCCGUUGGUGAUCGCGGGGGAGCACAACAUCCCGUGGCUGCUGCACCUGCCCGGCUCGGGGCGCCUCGUGGAGGGCGAGGUCUACGCGGUAGACGAGCGGAUGCUGCGCUUUCUGGAUGACUUCGAGAGUUGCCCGGCCCUGUACCAGCGCACGGUGCUGCGGGUACAGCUGCUGGAGGACCGGGCCCCGGGCGCAGAGGAGCCGCCAGCGCCCACCGCGGUGCAGUGCUUCGUGUACAGCAGGGCCACCUUCCCGCCGGAGUGGGCCCAGCUCCCGCACCAUGACAGCUACGACUCCGAGGGGCCGCACGGGCUGCGCUACAACCCCCGGGAGAACAGAUAAGGGGGACGGGCAGGGUGGGCCUAGGUUUGAGAGCCCUGGGGCUCCAAGAUGCGCCCAGCCCAUGCUGGGUGAAGGCGGAAGCCGAACAGGGCCCUUUCCAAUGAAUCUGCCGGAAAGGAACCAAUCUUUCAGUGGCAGCUGAUUUUACAAAUAAUGUUGAGAUACGAAUAGCAAGGUGCUUCCCUCCCAUCUUUCUACCUGGUAAGAAAAAUUUAGGAUUUUAACUCCCCUAAAUGACAUUUAGAGAACUCGUGUUAUGCCUAAUUCUUCUUCCUCCUCGUGUUGUUUCUGCUGUUGGCUCUGCUUUGAGCUCAAGAUAAUAAUAAAUAUUUAGGAUCAGUGUAAAGACUUGGUGUUGCCGCUAGAUUUUAGCAGCCCUACUAUACUGAUUCUGGCCUGUAACCCCUGAGAAAGCCGAUUUUACACGGCUGGGUAGAAUUUGUAGAAAAGAUCCACAGGGCAAGCAUGCUGUAUAUCAGAGUGCGUAUAGCACCAUUCUUCCUAAUUUUCAGAUCAAGCUUCACAGCAAAUAUUAAAGAUUAUUUAAAUUUGAAGUCGAUGUUUUGGGAAAUCAGAUAUAAAAGUGUUGGUACUGUGUUUGACCCCCACGUUUUUUGGUAUACUUAUUUGGUAGAAGGUUCUUUACAUUCUGAUCUAGCAAAAUAAUGAACACCCACUUGCUGGUAGACACAGCUGAGCGCCCGGACUUCAAGUGGAAGUUUAUCUGAGCCCAGAUCUCAGUAGCCAGACCCCGUCCCUGCCCCCUGAAGGGAGAGCAUUUGGGGGUGAGUCCUUUCAAAGAAGAGCCAAUGCAUUAGUAAUUUGUUCUUCAGGCCUGACAGAAGCUUAGCUUCCAAAUACAAACAGCACUUAAAAUAAUUUUAGCAAGGCACGAAGUACCAAUUACUACCCACCUCCAUCUGAUAAUUGUCAGCAUCGAUUCAACUCGGUGCACGGCUCUUGCUUCUGCUUCCCAGCAAAGUCUGAAAUGUAUUCCAAGGAUUUCAGAACCAAAUGAAAAUGCAGCUGCUGUGAUCUUUAGUAACCUCAUUCUCUGUUGGGAGAGCUCACUUACUCUUCAACUUAAUGGCAGACUGUGAUCGCUAACUGCAUCUGGCACAAAAACAUGAUCAUUAUUUUUAGCUUCUUUUGCUUAAUUGGAAACUUGCUUCACAAAAAACACAAAAAGGCUACGCUGGGUCUCAGCUGAUGAGCUCGUGGCGGCCCUGUGCUUGAUGAGGGCGGUGAGGCAGCCCAAGCUCCUUGUGACUGCCCUGGCUUGUGCAAUGGGGAAGGGACCAGGCAGCGCGCUCAUCCUCAAAACAAACAAAAACAGUGGAGACAGCACCCCCGGCCAACCAGGAAGCUUCAGGGUGACCUCCAGGGGAGUCAGCCACCAACAGUACACCCACAUAGAGACACAGCAGGAAAGGGAUUGCCAAAAUCUGCAUUUGCAGUCUCUGGUCCUUAGGAAGUUUUGAAAAUCAGCACCAGGAGUGAGGGCCUCACUUCUAGAAGUAGUAAGGCAAUCAGAUGAAAAAAUGGCAAGUGCUAAUUUAAUAAAGCAAGGCAGAGAACUGACUGACAUUUAUAUCAAUCUCUUAAAAGGAUCACAAAGAAAUGCUGGUAGUCUACUGGCAGAGCCUGUCGCCUAUGUGUACAUUGUCUUCAUUCAAAGAAAGGGCAAACUAAUAUUUAGACAAAUGCUCAGUUUUAUUGAUUUAAUUUUGACACUAGGGAAUCUCACAGCAGAAGUACAAAUCAUAUGUACAAGUAUUUAUAUCAAUGAAAAUUUCCAUUGGUGAUUUUUUGGCAGAAUAUUGGUCUUGACUCUGUGGAAUAAAUGACGACGUAAACGUAGCUGCACAGGGGUGUUCCUGUAUAAUGCUUGAAUCAAUUGUGUGUGAAAGCAUCAUGCAAAUGGCUAAUUAAAUUGGGUGAUGACUGAAA